GAGGACGACGUUCGGCCUGCGCAGUGAGAUGUUUGUCCGUCGCCGCCGCCGCCGCCAUCGCGGAGGAGCGCGAUAAAGGGAGCCGAGCCGGACGUGAGGGGGACCCCGCGGAGCCGCCGCGCCAGCGCAGCCCCCCAGCCGCAUCGGAGUCGCCAGAGUCCGAGCCGCCGCCGCCGCCGCCGCCGCCCCCGCCGCCGCCGCGGCUGCCCAGGGGCCGGCCAGCUCCCCAGCCCUGCCCGGGGGUCGCGCCGCCGCCGCCCCCAGCGUCGCCCCUAGCCUGCCUGCCCGCCUUAAAUGUGACACCGGCGUCGCGGAGCGCGACCUGAAGCCGCCGCCGGGGAGGGGACGAGCACCAUGUCGAAUCUGAGCAAAGGCACGGGCAGCCGGAAGGACACCAAGAUGCGGAUCCGGGCCUUUCCGAUGACCAUGGAUGAAAAAUAUGUAAACAGCAUUUGGGACCUUCUGAAAAAUGCAAUUCAAGAAAUCCAGCGUAAGAAUAACAGUGGUCUUAGUUUUGAGGAGCUCUAUAGAAAUGCAUAUACAAUGGUUUUGCAUAAACAUGGAGAAAAGCUCUACACUGGACUAAGAGAAGUUGUUACCGAACAUCUCAUAAAUAAGGUGCGAGAAGAUGUACUAAAUUCAUUGAAUAACAACUUUCUUCAAACGCUAAAUCAAGCUUGGAAUGAUCAUCAAACAGCUAUGGUGAUGAUUAGAGACAUACUAAUGUACAUGGACCGUGUGUAUGUACAACAAAAUAAUGUGGAGAACGUCUACAAUUUGGGAUUAAUUAUUUUUCGAGAUCAAGUUGUACGUUAUGGGUGUAUUAGGGAUCAUCUACGGCAAACUCUAUUGGAUAUGAUUGCAAGAGAGCGGAAAGGAGAAGUCGUAGACAGAGGCGCAAUAAGAAAUGCUUGCCAGAUGUUAAUGAUUUUAGGUCUCGAAGGAAGAUCAGUCUAUGAAGAAGAUUUUGAGGCUCCUUUUUUGGAAAUGUCUGCAGAAUUUUUUCAGAUGGAAAGCCAGAAAUUUUUAGCAGAAAAUAGUGCUUCAGUAUAUAUAAAGAAAGUAGAAGCUAGAAUUAAUGAAGAAAUAGAACGAGUGAUGCACUGCCUUGACAAAUCAACGGAAGAACCAAUUGUAAAGGUGGUUGAAAGGGAACUCAUUUCCAAGCACAUGAAGACUAUAGUAGAAAUGGAGAAUUCUGGGCUAGUACAUAUGUUGAAAAAUGGAAAGACAGAAGACCUUGGUUGCAUGUACAAGUUAUUUAGUCGUGUGCCAAAUGGUUUGAAAACAAUGUGUGAGUGUAUGAGUUCCUAUUUGAGGGAGCAAGGUAAAGCUCUUGUUUCUGAAGAAGGAGAAGGAAAGAAUCCUGUUGACUAUAUCCAGGGCUUAUUGGAUCUGAAGAGUAGGUUCGAUCGCUUCCUCCUGGAAUCAUUCAACAAUGACCGUCUCUUUAAACAAACUAUUGCGGGUGACUUUGAGUAUUUUCUCAACCUCAACUCCAGGUCUCCUGAAUACCUCUCAUUAUUUAUUGAUGAUAAGCUGAAAAAGGGAGUCAAAGGGCUAACAGAACAAGAAGUAGAAACAAUAUUGGAUAAAGCAAUGGUCCUUUUUAGGUUUAUGCAAGAAAAAGAUGUAUUUGAACGUUAUUAUAAACAACACUUGGCAAGGAGACUUCUCACAAAUAAAAGUGUUUCUGAUGACUCUGAAAAAAACAUGAUAUCUAAGUUAAAGACUGAAUGUGGAUGUCAGUUCACGUCAAAACUGGAAGGAAUGUUUAGGGAUAUGAGCAUCUCAAACACAACGAUGGAUGAAUUCAGGCAACAUCUACAGGCAACUGGUGUAUCUUUAGGUGGUGUUGAUCUUACAGUCCGGGUGCUCACGACAGGAUAUUGGCCCACUCAGUCAGCCACACCAAAGUGCAACAUCCCACCAGCACCAAGACAUGCUUUUGAGAUAUUCAGAAGGUUCUACUUAGCCAAACACAGUGGUCGACAGCUCACACUCCAGCAUCAUAUGGGUUCUGCAGAUCUCAAUGCCACAUUUUAUGGACCAGUUAAAAAGGAAGAUGGAUCUGAAGUUGGUGUUGGAGGUGCACAAGUAACUGGCUCUAAUACACGGAAGCACAUAUUGCAAGUUUCCACUUUCCAGAUGACCAUAUUAAUGCUCUUUAAUAAUAGAGAAAAAUACACAUUUGAGGAAAUUCAGCAAGAGACAGAUAUCCCUGAAAGAGAGCUUGUUAGAGCCCUACAGUCCCUCGCCUGUGGUAAACCAACACAGCGGGUUCUUACAAAAGAACCCAAAUCAAAGGAAAUAGAAAAUGGUCAUAUAUUUACAGUUAAUGAUCAAUUCACAUCCAAACUACACAGAGUCAAGAUUCAAACAGUUGCUGCCAAACAAGGUGAAUCCGACCCAGAGAGGAAAGAAACAAGGCAGAAAGUAGACGACGACAGAAAACAUGAGAUAGAAGCUGCUAUAGUGCGGAUAAUGAAAUCUAGAAAGAAGAUGCAGCACAAUGUUCUAGUAGCGGAGGUAACUCAGCAGUUGAAGGCGCGAUUCUUACCAAGUCCAGUUGUUAUUAAGAAACGUAUUGAAGGACUUAUUGAGAGAGAAUAUUUGGCACGAACACCUGAGGAUCGCAAAGUAUACACAUAUGUAGCAUAAAAUGCGUUCAGAAAUUUGAUUUAUUCUUGGACUGUACUCUUCGCAUGGACUGGGAAGUUCUUUUAAAUCAUUAAAUAUUAAGACGACCAUCUCUUCUAUUAAAUUACAGUACAUGUUCUAGACCAUUGAGAUCAAGCCUUUACUCCCUUUGAGAGUUUCCAACAUCAGUUGAUUGAGCUUCAGGCUUUACAACGUUUAUCCCUGUAGAGAUCAUCUUUACAGUUCCUCGGGAAAAUGUGAAUGUGCUGCGUUUUGUUUUCUUUACUGUAUGAAAACAGGAAAAUAAAAGAGAAAUUUAGAAAAUACAGCUCAUUACAAUAAAAUUGUUGGAUUUCAUUUCCCCAGGUCUUCAGUGUUGAUGUAAAUGUGUUUUGUAGUGUUGCUUAGCACUUUGCGCAUUGUGUAAGUUGGGUAACAAAAAUGGCAAAAGAAAUGCAGAUUUCCCAGUUAUCUUGCUCUGAAGACAUUUCUUUAGCUAGUCUUAUUUAAUUUUAAAGGUUUGAUAAAUAUACAAAGACCCAAGCAUACAAUUUGAGCAUGCUGUAUUCUACCACUUGCACUUACUCAUCUUCUAGCCUUAUGACCAGGAACCUUUGUUUUGGGCUCAAGUACACAUCCUGAUUUGGUUUCUCCCUGUUGUAAUUUGAGAUUUCCCAAAUUAAGUCUUAUAAUGAUUAGGUUUUGUUCUGAGUUAUUUCUAGAGAAAGAAAGUAUUUUAGUAUGUGUAAAUUGUACAAUAAUUUUUUUGCUGUUGUACUCACUGCUAAUAGUGGAUUGUAUAGGGUGGUGUUUUUAUUUCAUUUAUUGUAGACAAAAAUAAUGAAUUUAGUAUACACAUACCCACUAAUUCAAGUAUGUCAGAGCACAAAGUUGGCAGCUGGUUAUAUUUAAUUCAGCCCCUCUGAAAAGCACAUACAGUCUAUACUUUGUUUAUAAAUACCCUAGGUCCUCCCUGCCCCUAAAUAUAUAUUUUGGUGAAGCUGUGGUGCACUAUUAAUUUUCUGUUUCAAAAUGCAAUCUAAAGAUGCAAUAAAUAUGAUGACCUUGAUAGUUUUAAUGAAAUCUUCAAUUCUUGCAGCUGUGUUUUGGAAAGUGAUUAAGCAAUAUUUCUCAAACCUGAUGAUUCUUGGAUAUUUAGCUAUUGUCCUCCAAAGAGUCAUCGUUUCACGUUUUCAAACAUGUGCUUUGUGCUGAAGAUUCUUGUCAGAUAUCCUGUGCUUCCAGAGUAUUUUUAUCUUCAAUUUUAUUUAAUUUUGUUUCAUUUUGUUUUCAUAAGACAAUGUUUCAGAUAUGUAAUGGGGCAAACCACUAUAGAUUUCUGUUGGAUAGAAAAAUGAAAUGUUACUAAUAAGUUUAAAUUGACCCUUCGUUGACUAUCAGUACUGUUGAUACAUUUAUUAGAAUGUAUGUCUCAGAAGAUGGUUUCUGUUUAAAUUUAUGGUCAAGUUACAACAACUGAAUUCUAAUAUGGAUUAAAAACUCCACAUAAAUAUUUUUCCCCAUGCGUCUUGGGUUAUAAUUUUCCUUUUAGACUUGCAAAUAUGCUUUUAUUGCAAUUUUGUCUCCAUCUGUACUGUAGAAUUACAAGCCUUGUGCUCUUUAUCUCUACAUUUUCCACUUCUACAUGAUGCAAUUAAGAUGCCAAUGAAAAGUAUUGUGAACAUUAUUCUCAGGACACUUUUACCAUACUUGAGUAGUACUAAGUCAGGUGUAACAUGGAAAGCUAAGGGUUUCACCUUCUGAUUUUGACAUAAUUGGAAAUUUUCUAUAAUGGUAAGAUGUUUAUAGGAAAGUAAUGGUAGUUCAUGUUUGAGAAUUUUUUUAUUGCUUUCAUUUCCCAGUUAAAUGAUAUUUAACACCUGGGAAAACAGGACAGCUCAGAUUGUCGAGUUAGUAAACAUGAGCGAUGUAAAAACUUUAUUUGAAAUCUCCUAAGUGAGACAUUAAACAUUUUAGUGCUAGUUUAAGCCAUUAAAAGUAAAGUUUAAGUUUACGUCAUUGUCUCAAGUGUGGCUGUAAAAAUCAGAUCUAGAGUUUAGAGACAUACUUGUUAACUUUGGAGCACAGGUUUGAUAUUUAUGCUUCUAAAUACAUUAAAACAUUUCUGAAUUGCAGUUGAAUGGUUGGAGAUUGCUGGCGAUGUGAUGCUGCACUGAAAAAACUGGUCACACAAAAUGUUUAUAUGUUUGACUGCAUAAGUAUUAUUUUAGGUCAUAAAGGUUAUAACAAAAUACAUUUAACAUUGCUUUCUUUUUAGCAAGAGGUCACAGAUGCUAUUUUUUCUCAGUUUUUAAUGCUUUAAUUUGAAAGAAAAAUGCAUCCUAACCAUUCCAUCCUGUUGGUGCAGAGAAAUUUUGGUGAUUUAUUAGAAGACUUUUAAGGAGGGUGGAUACAUAGUUUUUCAACUGCAAAAAUCAUGUCAUCUCUUCAGUAACUGUUAAAGUGUAAUUCUCUGCCUUCAUUAUCAAGUCCAGGACAGUGUUUAUUUUGAAUCGUUAACAUUAUUUAAAGACUGAAAAUUCAUUGCAAUUAGGGAACGCACAGCCUCACAAAAAGUGGUUGUGAUUGCAAGGAUUCUUUAUGUCAGUGAACUUAAAAAGGGAAUGGGGGAAGAGAUGCAUGCCUUUCUAAAGGUAUGCUAGAGUCACCUGUGUAGCAUUGUAAUUAUGUACUAUCAAACCCCCAAGAUGCUGAUGAUAGGCCUUCUCUGUAAGAAUCCUUCUCAUAGUGAAGCACUGUUGAUGUUUUGUUCACCGGAUAUGUUGGGUAGCAGAAAAGGCCUAGAACCAGUUUUAAGAUUAUGCCUACAUCUCUAGAAGACUAGUACACUGGCAUCAUCUUAGGUUUCUAAAUAUUAUUUAAUUCCUUAAUUUGGAAAGCAGUUUUAAUGUUUACAGUUUAAGAUACUCAUUUUCAGUAACUAGUGUUAAAGAUUUUUAUCUUUGCCUGUCUACUGUAACUUAAGACUUUCAUAGAAUAAUUUUUUAUAGAGUAUAUGGUAUAUUGUGUCAAUCUUGGAAGGAAAGCUGUUGCAUAUCAAUUGUAGGUCAUGUAUUUUACUAUAUGUUGCAUAGUAUUUUGCAUUCUGUAAAUACGAAUGUUAAAACAUUUCAGGUCAGCAAAAUUAGAAGUCAUUUCUAGUCCUCAAAGCAGAAAUAAUUAGAAAUGUUAACAUUUAAGUGCUUAUCAUAUGCCAGAUACUAUUCUGAAUAUUUUAUGUAUAUUCAUUCAUUUAGUUGUCAUAUUGGCUUUAUGUGACAUAACUGUCAUUAUACCAGUGUUGUCCAAGGUUGCUAGCAGGAAAUGGCAGAGCCAGGAGUUGGACCUAGGUUUAAUCCUAUCCAUAUUCCAUGUUACAAAUUGACAUGAUUUUCCAUAUUAAAAAAUUUUCAUUUAUUUUGUACCUCAUUCACAUGAAUAGUAAUGUGACAAACUAAAGUUAAUACAUGAAGCAUUGCAAUAUGGAAUUUUGCACAUUUUUGUUAGCUUUACAUUAUUUGCUGAUACCAACUUUUGGUAGGAAGGAAAACAGGGAAGGUGAUUGCUGCUAUUCUGGAAUGUGUCCAUUGAAAAGAAAAUAGGCGCUUUGUCUCCUACAAUCUUAGAGAAAGUUUUACAUACUUAAGUGGGUACCACAGAUAGGCAUGUACCUUAAAUUCAAAUCUACAGUUUUACAAAAUGUUUUCCUUUGUGUGCCUUUCCUAUGUCAAAUUAGCCAGAAGGAAGAAGAGACGUUAAGAAUGGCAGAUAAAUUUAACAGGUAAUGAUACAGAGAUUGGCCAUUACGCCAGCUCUCAGGAGAAAAACAACUAGGAUGUCUUGAAACCCGUGCAUUUAAUUUUAGAAAUGGCAAAUUUGUAAGCGUGUCAUUUAAGUAAUUUGAUGCUCAGUUUUAGGGUCUAAGUUGACCUCGAGUGAGCCAUGCAAAAAUAGCUUUAAAAUUAUACAUGAGCAGCUCAAAGUAAACGUGUAUUUUUUAGUAACAAUGAAAUUGUCAAAUUUCAAGAUUUUAAUAACAGGACAGUUCAACUAAUAAACUUUAUUGCAUACAAGAUUUAUUGCAAUGUGGGAAAAUUAAAAUUCUCAGUCUCAGAA